AGCUGCGGCGCGUGACGCGGGGCGCGCGGCUCCGUCGGCUACCGCGGGCGGGCGCAGGCGACGGGCACGGCGGGCGAGCGGGCGGUAUGGCGGCGGCGGGGCCCGCGGCGGGGCCGACGGGGCCCGAGCCCAUGCCGAGCUACGCGCAGCUAGUGCAGCGCGGCUGGGGCAGCGCGCUGGCGGCGGCGCGGGGCUGCACGGACUGCGGCUGGGGGCUGGCGCGUCGCGGCCUGGCUGAGCACGCGCACCUGGCGCCGCCCGAGCUGCUGCUGCUGGCGCUCGGCGCGCUGGGCUGGACCGCCCUGCGCUCCGCGGCCACUGCGCGCCUCUUUCGGCCCCUGGCGAAGCGGUGCUGCCUCCAGCCCAGAGAUGCCGCCAAGAUGCCCGAGAGCGCUUGGAAGUUUCUCUUCUACCUGGGCAGCUGGAGCUACAGUGCCUACCUGCUGUUUGGCACCGACUACCCCUUCUUCCAUGACCCACCAUCUGUCUUCUACGACUGGACGCCGGGCAUGGCAGUGCCACGGGACAUUGCAGCCGCCUACCUGCUCCAGGGAAGCUUCUAUGGCCACUCCAUCUACGCUACGCUAUACAUGGACACCUGGCGCAAGGACUCGGUGGUCAUGCUGCUCCACCACGUGGUCACUCUCAUCCUCAUCGUCUCCUCCUACGCCUUCCGGUACCACAAUGUGGGCAUCCUUGUGCUCUUCCUGCACGAUAUCAGUGACGUGCAGCUUGAGUUCACCAAGCUCAACAUUUACUUCAAGUCCCGCGGCGGCUCCUACCAUCGGCUGCAUGCCUUGGCAGCAGACUUGGGCUGCCUCAGCUUCGGCUUCAGCUGGUUCUGGUUCCGCCUCUACUGGUUCCCGCUCAAGGUCCUGUAUGCCACCAGUCACUGCAGUCUGCGCACGGUGCCUGACAUCCCCUUCUACUUCUUCUUCAAUGCGCUCCUGCUGCUGCUCACCCUUAUGAACCUCUACUGGUUCCUGUACAUCGUGGCGUUUGCAGCCAAGGUGUUGACAGGCCAGGUGCACGAGCUGAAGGACCUGCGGGAGUAUGACACAGCCGAGGCCCAGAGCCUGAAGCCCAGCAAAGCCGAGAAGCCACUGAGGAACGGCCUGGUGAAGGACAAGCGCUUCUGAACCCCUCGGCCCCGCCCCCGUGGACCCGGCCCCACCCCGAAUACCCCGGCCACGCUCCCCGUCCUUGGCCGCCCCUCCACCCCCUCCAACUCUGCUCCUCUAGGGCCGCCGCCACCUCCCCUGGGACCCCGCCCCCUCAUCCUGCCUCCAGUUCCCGGCCACGCCCCCCAGGACCCCUGCCCCUCCGGGGACACCGGCCCCGCCCUCAGCCCACUGGUCCCGGGCCGCCGCGGACCCUGCGCACUCUCUGGUCAUCGCCUGGGAGGAAGAUGCCACCGCCGCAGCAAGGUCCCUGCGGCCACCACCUCCUCCUCCUCCUGGCCCUGCUGCUGCCCUCGCUGCCCCUGACCCGCGCCCCCGUGCCCCCAGGCCCAGCCGCCGCCCUGCUCCAGGCUCUAGGACUGCGCGAUGAGCCCCAGGGUGCCCCCAGGCUCCGGCCGGUUCCCCCGGUCAUGUGGCGCCUGUUUCGACGCCGGGACCCCCAGGAGACCAGGUCUGGCUCGCGGCGGACGUCCCCAGGGGUCACCCUGCAACCGUGCCACGUGGAGGAGCUGGGGGUCGCCGGAAACAUCGUGCGCCACAUCCCGGACCGCGGUGAGUGGGGCUUUCGCUGGGGACACUGGUCCUGGAGGCCAGACCUCGCAGGGCGAGCCUCGAGAGUGGCCCGGGGAUGCCCGAGCAGCUCCGAGGGUCCCCACCCGCCCUGUCCAGGCUACUAGCAACUUCGGCCACCGCACCUCACCCUUUCCUCGUCAUCUGCUGCACGCCGGGGACACAUGUCAGGGGGUUCCCAAGACCAGUCCUUCUGCUUGAUGCUGAAGCCCUGUCCCCACCCCAUGCCCACCCCCACCUCUUGACACUAAUGCCUUCCUGCAGAUGCCAUCCCCACACCCUAGCAUGGCUUCCCCAGGGGCCCAGGUUCUGGCUCAUGUCUCCCACUUCGGCCACCCCUCCUCCUAUGCCCCCCGCCGAGGGCAGCCCACCCCCCCCGCCGCACCCCGCAGGGCGCCUUCCUUGGAACUCAUGCCCUGCCCCCACUCCAUCAGCCCACCCCGCCGCUUCACACCCUUCCCACAGACGGUGCGCCCCGAGCCCCAGCGUUCACCUUCCUCCCUGUCCCUAACCGAGACCCCAUGGGCAGGCCGGGGACGCAGCGCGAGCCGAGUUCCUGUUCCUACCUCCCCAGGUGCGCCCACCCGGGCCUCGGAGCCUGCCUCGGCCGCGGGGCAUUGCCCUGAGUGGACAGUCGUCUUCGACCUGUCGGCUGUGGAACCCGCUGAGCGCCCGAGCCGGGCCCGCCUGGAGCUGCGUUUCGCGGCGGCGGCGGCGGCAGCCCCGGAGGGCGGCUGGGAGCUGAGCGUGGCGCAAGCGGGCCAGGGCGCGGGCGCGGACCCCGGGCCGGUGCUGCUCCGCCAGUUGGUGCCCGCCCUGGGGCCGCCAGUGCGCGCGGAGCUGCUGGGCGCCGCUUGGGCUCGCAACGCCUCAUGGCCGCGCAGCCUCCGCCUGGCGCUGGCGCUACGCCCCCGGGCCCCUGCCGCCUGCGCGCGCCUGGCCGAGGCCUCGCUGCUGCUGGUGACCCUCGACCCGCGCCUGUGCCACCCCCUGGCCCGGCCGCGGCGCGACGCCGAACCCGUGUUGGGCGGCGGCCCCGGGGGCGCUUGUCGCGCGCGGCGGCUGUACGUGAGCUUCCGCGAGGUGGGCUGGCACCGCUGGGUCAUCGCGCCGCGCGGCUUCCUGGCCAACUACUGCCAGGGUCAGUGCGCGCUGCCCGUCGCGCUGUCGGGGUCCGGGGGGCCGCCGGCGCUCAACCACGCUGUGCUGCGCGCGCUCAUGCACGCGGCCGCCCCGGGAGCCGCCGACCUGCCCUGCUGCGUGCCCGCGCGCCUGUCGCCCAUCUCCGUGCUCUUCUUUGACAACAGCGACAACGUGGUGCUGCGGCAGUAUGAGGACAUGGUGGUGGACGAGUGCGGCUGCCGCUAACCCGGGGCGGGCAGGGACGCGGGCCCAACAAUAAAUGCCGCGUGGUCUGCUC